GUUGGACGUGGUCAGCACAGGGGCCGGCACCACGGGGUUAUCGAAGCAGCUGUCAAGAUGCUGGGGUCCCUGGUGUUGAGGAGAAAAGCACUGGCGCCACGGCUACUCCUCCGGCUGCUCAGGUCCCCAACGCUCCGGGGCCAUGGAGGUGCUUCCGGCCGGAAUGUGACUACUGGGAGUCUCGGGGAGCCGCAGUGGCUGAGGGUAGCCACCGGGGGGCGCCCUGGAACAUCGCCGGCCUUGUUCUCCGGACGUGGGGCAGCCACCGGGGGGCGCCAGGGAGGACGCUUCGAUACCAAAUGCCUCGCGGCUGCCACUUGGGGACGCCUUCCUGGUCCCGAAGAAACACUCCCAGGACAGGACAGCUGGAACGGGGUCCCCAGCAGGGCCGGACUGGGCAUGUGCGCCCUGGCCGCAGCGCUGGUGGUUCAUUGCUACAGCAAGAGUCCGUCCAACAAGGAUGCAGCCCUGUUGGAAGCUGCCCGUGCCAACAAUAUGCAAGAAGUCAGCAGAUGCAGAAACAGGCUUAGAGAGCAGGAGCUAUCAUGUAAAUGAAGGAAGCAGUUGAGAUUCAGAGAGGCUAAGUCAUUCAUUCAUCCACCACUCCUCACUUACCCCAAGAGACUGCAAAGAAUGAUGCUCAGUCAAGAAGCUGGGCAGGGCUGAAUGCUGGAGUCUCACUGAAGAACACCAAGAUUUCCUCCUCUGAAUGGCCCCUCAGGCUGUUGUCAGAAGGUGCAGAUGUCAAUGCAAAGCACAGACUUGGCUGGACAGCACUCAUGGUGGCAGCCAUCAACCGAAACAACAGUGUGGUACAGGUCCUGCUUGCUGCUGGGGCUGAUCCAAACCUUGGAGAUGAUUUCAGCAGUGUUUACAAGACUGCCAAGGAACAGGGAAUCCAUUCUUUGGAAGAUGGGGGACAGGACGGUGCAAGCCGGCACAUCACAAACCAGUGGACAAGUGCCCUGGAGUUCAGGAGAUGGCUAGGACUCCCCGCUGGCGUCCUGAUCACCCGAGAGGAUGACUUCAACAACAGGCUGAACAACCGCGCCAGUUUCAAGGGCUGCACGGCCUUGCACUAUGCUGUUCUUGCUGAUGACUACCGCACUGUCAAGGAGCUGCUUGAUGGAGGAGCCAACCCCCUGCAGAGGAAUGAAAUGGGACACACACCCUUGGAUUAUGCCCGAGAAGGGGAAGUGAUGAAGCUUCUGAGGACUUCUGAAGCCAAGUACCAAGAGAAGCAGCGGAAGCGUGAGGCUGAGGAGCGGCGCCGCUUCCCCCUGGAGCAGCGACUAAAGGAGCACAUCAUUGGCCAGGAGAGCGCCAUCGCCACAGUGGGUGCUGCGAUCCGGAGGAAGGAGAAUGGCUGGUACGAUGAAGAACACCCUCUGGUCUUCCUCUUCUUGGGAUCAUCUGGAAUAGGAAAAACAGAGCUGGCCAAGCAGACAGCCAAAUAUAUGCACAAAGAUGCUAAAAAGGGCUUCAUCAGGCUGGACAUGUCCGAGUUCCAGGAGCGACACGAGGUGGCCAAGUUUAUUGGGUCUCCACCAGGCUACGUUGGCCAUGAGGAGGGUGGCCAGCUGACCAAGAAGUUGAAGCAGUGCCCCAAUGCUGUGGUGCUCUUUGAUGAAGUAGACAAGGCCCAUCCAGAUGUGCUCACCAUCAUGCUGCAGCUGUUUGAUGAGGGCCGGCUGACAGAUGGAAAAGGGAAGACCAUUGAUUGCAAGGACGCCAUCUUCAUCAUGACCUCCAAUGUGGCCAGCGACGAGAUCGCACAGCACGCGCUGCAGCUGAGGCAGGAAGCUUUGGAGAUGAGCCGUAACCGUAUUGCCGAAAACCUGGGGGAUGUCCAGAUAAGUGACAAGAUCACCAUCUCAAAGAACUUCAAGGAGAAUGUGAUUCGCCCUAUCCUGAAAGCUCACUUCCGGAGGGAUGAGUUUCUGGGACGGAUCAAUGAGAUCGUCUACUUCCUCCCCUUCUGCCACUCGGAGCUCAUCCAACUCGUCAACAAGGAACUAAACUUCUGGGCCAAGAGAGCCAAGCAAAGGCACAACAUCACGCUGCUCUGGGACCGCGAGGUGGCAGAUGUGCUGGUCGACGGCUACAAUGUGCACUAUGGCGCCCGCUCCAUCAAACAUGAGGUAGAACGCCGUGUGGUGAACCAGCUGGCAGCAGCCUAUGAGCAGGACCUGCUGCCAGGGGGCUGUACUUUGCGCAUCACGGUGGAGGACUCAGACAAGCAGCUACUCAAAAGCCCAGAACUGCCCUCACCCCAGGCUGAGAAGCGCCUCCCCAAGCUGCGUCUGGAGAUCAUCGACAAGGACAGCAAGACUCGCAGACUGGACAUCCGGGCACCACUGCACCCUGAGAAGGUGUGCAACACCAUCUAGCAGCCACCUGCCUGCUCCUAUGUGCCCUCACCAUCCAAUAAAGGCCCCUUGGCUGUGGCAUGGCAACUGACUUACCUUCCCCUCAUGCCGCUCCCAUCUCUACCCAGUCUCAGGCCUGCUUACCUCCUCACAGCCCAUGAAGACCCCUUCUCAGCCCCAAAACCUGAAGGAGGAAUUUCGCCCUACUCUGGCCCCUUUGUUGUGGGCCCAUAACCUGCUAACAAGCCUUCAGGAGAGGAGCUGCCUUUCCACCCCCUUCAAGGCAAGGAGGGAUGGAGGUCCCUUAUUUCCUUCAGAAUGAUCCCCAUCCCCCAUAGUCGCCAGACUUUCUCAUGUUCCCAGGAAGCUCAGAAGUAUGGCAGCUAAGAACACAGCUGGCUGGAAGAAGACAGGGACCAGACUGAACUGCCACCCUCUGCUAGUCCUCAUGCAACUCAGUCCCCAGAAUGGCUCCACUGGGAGUGGAGGAAGAGCUCAGAGGCCCAGGUGCAGAUAGUUCUGCAAUUUAGUCUGUAGCCUCCUCGUUCCCUACCCUAAAAUUCUAAGGGGAAGGGACCCAUAGAGGCUUGCCUGUUUCCGCUACUAUAUUAUGCCCAGUGUUCCUCCUCACCCCACGUCCUGGGGUCAGGCCAGACCAUGUUUCGUCAGCCUUGGGGACUAGGCCAGUGUUGGGCACCUCCAGGAGGAGGCCUGACUGGUUCAUUACCCUCCCCUACUCAGACUGAGCAGCAGUCCCAGAUAACCAAGCAAGCUCAGCUCUGUGGGGGCCUCCUUCAAAAGACCAACAUCGCAGACAUUAGGAAGCUGUAGGAAGAGAGAUCAUGGGUUUGACCUCUGCCCACAUGGCCAUGGAGUCAGCCUCAGCCCUGUCUGUACUGCUCGUCCAGCUAAACGAGCCUGGAAUAAACAUGCAGUUUAUUCAGUCUGCAUGUUAGUCACAAAGCAGAGGGUCUGGACACCGUCCCCCAAGGGCAUUUCACAGACCAGCCAAUGUUUCAAGCCCACCUUAGCCAGGCACAGUAAGGCCUGGUGCAUCCUUGGGCACCAUCUACAGUAGCCACUGCUGAUAAGCAGUCCACCCACCUUCCCCCACAGGCCCUUCAUGGAACCCUCGCGUAGUGUUAGCUAGUCUUUCAGGAAGCAGAGAAUGGGGCCAGGAAUCAAAGUCCCUUGGGUAAUGGAAGCAUGUCCUAACAGUAUGGUGGGUAUGAGGCAGUCAGAAUCCAGGGUGUGAGCUCCAGCAGAUGCUUGGAUCACUGUCUACCCCUCAGGGGCUGCUGCUCCCUACCUCACUGACUGCCUUUUUUUUUUUUUUUUUUUUUUUGAGACAGAGUCUCACUCUGUCCCCCAAGCUGGAGUGCAGUGGCGCGAUCUCGGCUCACUGCAAGCCCUGCCUCCCAGGUUCACGCCAUUCUCCUGCCUCAGCCUCCCGAGUAGCUGGGACUACAGGUGCCCACCACCACGCCCGGCUACCUUUUUGUAUUUUUAGUAGAGACAGGGUUUCACCAUGUUAGCCAGGAUGGUCUCAAUCUCCUGACCUUGUGAUCUGCCUGCCUCGGCCUCCCAAAGUGCUGGGAUUACAGGCAUGAGCCACUGGACCCGGCCUGCUUUUCAUUGUUUUUUACUUUUUGUUUUGAAAUAAUUUUAGACUUAGAGAAAGUUGCAGAAAUAGUAGAAAAUUCCCAUGUAUCUUUCAUCUAGCAUCUCCCAAUGAUUACAUCCUACAAAGCCAUACUGUAGUUUAUCAAAACCAGGAAAUUGCCGGGUGUGGUGGCUCAUGCCUGUAAUUCCAGCACUUUGGGAGGCUGAGGCAGGCAGAUUACCUGAGGUCAGGAGUUCGAGACCAGCCUGGCCAACAUGGUGAAACCCUGUCUGUACUAAAAAUACAAAAAUUAGCCAGGCCCGCUGGUGCCCACCUGUAAUCCCAGCUACUUGGGAGGCUGAGGCAGGAGAAUCACUUGAGCCCAGGAGGCGGAGGUUGCAGUGAGCUGAAAUCACGCCACUGCACUCCAGCCUGGGCGACAGAGUGAGACUCCGUCUCAAAAAAAGAAAACCAGGAAGUUAACAUUGAUAAACUACUACUAACUAAUCUACGGACAUUCAAAUUUUGCCAGUUUUCCCGAUGAUGUCCUUUGUCUGGUCCAGGGUCCCAUAUUGCAUUUUGUUGUGGUGUUUCCUUCAUCUCUGUCAGCCUGUGACAGUUUCUUGGUCUUUAUCUUUCAUGACCUUGACACUUUGGAAGAGUCCAGGCCAGUUAUUUUAUAGAAUAUUCCCCAGUUUUAGUUUGUUUAAUGUUUUUACAUGAUAUGAUUGAGGAUCUGCAUUUUUGCCAAGACAACCACAGAAGUGAUACUGUGCUAUUCUUAGUGCCUCCUAGCGGAGGGUGGUGGUAACUUUUUGUUUUGGUUUUUUUUUUUUUUUUGAGACGGAGUCCCGCUCUGUCACCCAGGAUGGAGUGCAGUGGCGCAAUCUCGGCUCACUGCAACCUCUGCCUCCUGGGUUCAAAGUGAUUCUCCUGCCUCAGCCUCCUGAGUAGCUGGGAUUGCAGGUGCCCACCACCACACCCAGCUAAUUUUUGUAUUUUUAGUAGAGACAGGUUUUCGCCAUGUUGGCCAGGCUGGUCUUGAACUCCUGACCUCAGGUGAUCCACCCACCUCGGCCUCCCAAAGUGCUGAGAUUACAGGCAUGAGCCACCACACCUAGACUAGGUGGUGGUAACUUUGAUCACAUGGCUAAGGUGGUGUGUGCCAGGUUUCUCCACUGUAAAAUUAGGAAUUUUCCCUUUGAAAUUAACAAGAAUCUUCCACUUUGAAGCUAUGUGAAUGUCUUAUUCUUAAAAUUUUGCCUACUGAUUUUCAUUUCCAUCAUCAAUGAUUCUUGCUUAUAACAGGUAUUAAUGUUAUGCUUGCCUAAUGGUGACUUUGUUUCAUUAUUUUACCUGUAUUUAUUAAUUGGUAUUCUACUAUAAGGAAGAGCUGUCCCUUUUCCCCAUUUAUUUAUUUGAUAAUUUAUAUCAGUAUGAAUGAGUGGAUAUCUGUUUUAUUCUACAGGCUACAAUCUAAUGCUAACAGUUUAUUUGGUUGCUCAAAUUGGCUCAGAUUUGGCCAGUGAGAACUCAUUGAAGUUGGCACUGUGUUGUUUCGACAUUGCCCCUGUCACUUUUUAAGCAUUUUCUGGCACCACAAGAUGUUUCAGGCUUCCUCACAUUUUCCCUAUCUCAGCCCUGGCAUCAGUCAUUCUCUAAGAAGCUCCCAGUUCCUUUUAUUCCAGAAAAAAGGAACUUAGAAACCAAGUUGUUUCUUGAUGCCACUGGAAACCAAGAUCUGGACAGAAUAUAUACUCCUGGCUAGAGUAUCAUUGGCGGAGUGUCAUUGCUUGUAGGCCUGCUCAGCAGACAGAGCUAGAAAACAUAUAUGUAUAUAUGUUAAAACAUGCAAAUACAAGCACCUGAAUUUAUUAUUCUAUCCAUCUGUAUGUUAUUAAAAACCGUGAGCCAGGUAUGGUGGCUCGUGCCUGUAUCCCAGGACUUUGGGAGGCCAAAGUGGGAGGAUCACUUGAGCCCAGGAGUUCAAGACCAGCCUGCGCAUCAUAGCAAGACCUCAUCCUCCAAACGUUUAAAAAAUAAAAAAUUAGCCAGGCAUGGUGGUGCAUUCCUGUAAUCCUAGCUACGUAGGAGGCUGAGGCAGGAGGAUCGCUUGAGUUCAGAAGGUUGAGGCUGUAGUGAACUGUGAUUGUACCACUGCACUGCAGCCUGAGUGACAGAGCAAGACUCCGUUUCAUAUUUUUAAAAAUAAAUAAAAAUCAUGAGUUUAGAUACGGUUUUAAUUCAAUACCAUAGGGUUUGCGACUGCCAUUUUUAUAACCUUACUAUUCUUUUUCUGCUUUUUCUCCUGCUAUCUCUGUUUCUGCUCCUUUCUAUUUGAUGUUUAGACUUCCCAUAGAGGCUCUAGUUAAGUCAGCUAGUAACCAGCCUGUGUGCAGUAUUCCUACUAGAUAGAGGUCUUAUGCCCGGCUGUCAGUCCGUUGGUUCAGUUAACUGUGGCCAGGAAUACUAGGCAUAUAACUUAAAAUCAGAUAACUUUUAUACAAGAAAAGCCAAUGGCCACCUUCCUGAGAAUAGGAUAAGGAGACAGGGGUAGAACCUUAGAUUCUAAGGAACCUAAUUAAGAAUCACUUCUGGCCGGGCGUGGUGGCUCAUGCCUGUAAUCCCAACACUCUGGAGGCCAUGUAGGGGCAGAUCACGAGAUCAAGAGAUUGAGACCAUCCUGACCAACAUGGUGAAACCCCAUCUCUACUAAAAAUACAAAAAUUAGCCAGGCGUGGUGGCGGGCGCCUGUAGUCUCAGCUACUCGGGAGGCUGAGGCAGGAGAAUCGCUUGAACCCGGGAGGUGGAGGUUGCAGUGAGCCGAAAUUGUGCCACUGCACUCCAGCCUGGUGACAGAGCCAGCCUCCGUCUCCAACAAAAACAAACAAAAAAAGAAUUACUUCUUCCAGAGAUUCUCUGCCAGAACUCCUAGGUGGUGUUGGACCCAUAUCUUUUACUUCCAUAGCAUCCCAGGCUCAGCUCACUUGUCCUACUUGUUCUGUGUCUUCAUCACUAGAAUGUAAGUUCUAAGAGGGCAGAUGCCAAGCUGUUCAGCCAUUCACAGAACCUGGCACAGUGCAGGCAUAUGACAGAUGUUCCUUUAUUAUUAUACUUGGGUGAGUGGAUGGGACCUGCAGCAAGUGCAGAUCUUCUCAGUGGGCUCUGGAACAGAAAAGUAUUGUUUGUUUGCUCAGCAUAUUUUUAUUUGUCCCAUGUUGCUGUGGCCAGGAUUUGAGCUCUGAGACAAUGCAGCAAGGUGAGACCCAGAUUUCUUUUGUUUUGUUUUGUUUUUUGAGACAGAGUCUUGCUCUGUCGCCCAGGCUGGAGUGCGGUGGUGCAAUCUUGGCUCACUGCAACCUCCACCUCCAGUUCAAGCAGGUCUCAUGCCUCAGCCUCCUCAGUAGCUGGGACUACAGGCAUAUGCCACCAUACCCAGCUAAUUUUUUUUGUAUUUUUAGUAAAGACGGGGUUUCACCAUGUUUGCCAGGCUAGUCUCAAACUCCUGGUCUCAAGUGAUCCACCCACCUUGGCCUCCCAGAGUGCUGAGAUUACAAGCGUCAACGACUGUACCCGGCCCCAAAUUCCUUAUUGAGGAUCCUAGAAUACAUGAGACCAGACUUGGAAAUGAAAGUGUAACAUGUUUAUUGUUCAAAAAGAAAAACUCAAAGGUGUGUAGUGAUUUUAAAAUUUAGGGAAAUUCCUCAAUAUAGUGAAAGAAGAAAAACAAGAAAGAAAUUUAGGAAAGAAACACACUUAAACCAUAAAAAAUAGAAAAUGGACCAAUAAAGAUAAAAGCUAAACUUAACAAGGUAGGAAAAAGAAAAAGAAUAAAUUAAAAAAUUCUUUGAAAGCACCAAUAAAAUAGAUAAAACCUCCUGAGCCUGAUAAAAGGGGAAAGGAGCCAAAAAAAUUAACAAAAUUAGGCAUGAGAAAUUAGACAUAACCAUAUAUAUUGAGGAAUUGAGAAGAAGAAUAGAACUCUAUGGCAACAAAUUUGAAAUCAGAGGAAAUGGAUAAUUUCCCAGCAAACACUGAUCCUAGAAAUAGUUUGAAUAGGCCAGUUGGUUACCCAAGAAGAAACUGGAAAGGUGGUUAAAAUUUUAUCCUUUUUGAGCACCAUAAGAUGGUGAAAAAUAAAUAAAAUUUUAUCCUUGUAAAAGAUUGAUGGCCAGGCAUGGUGGUGGCCCACACCUGUAAUCCUAGCACUUUGGAAGGCCAAGGCAGGCAGAUCACUUGAGCCCCGGAGUCUGAGACCAGCCUGGGCAACAUGGCAAGACCCCACCUCUACUAAAAAUACCAAAAUUAGCCAGGCAUGAUGGUGCUUGCCUGUAGUCAACAGCUACUUGGGAGGCUGAGGUGGGGAAGAUGGUUUAAGCCCAGGAGGCAGAGGUUGCAGUGAGCCAAGACUGUGCUGCUGCACUCCAGCCUGGGUGACAGAGCGAGACCAUGUCCCAAAAAUAAAAAAUUGUUUUUAAUUAAACUUUUUAAUUGAAAAAUAUAUGGGAAAUUGUACAAAUCACAAGUAUGCAGCUCAGUGAAUGAUUACAAAGUAAACACACUCCUAUAGCCAUCACUCAACCCCCAAAAUAGAUGAGUUUUAACUAUUAUUGUACUCAAACCUGAUAAAGUGCCAGAAAGAAUGCUAUAGCCUAAUCUCACCUAUGGCCAUAGAUGCAAAAAUCCCAAAUAAAAUCAAGUUGAAUUGCACACUCUGAUUACAUAAGGUUUAUUUUAGCAAUGCAAGGCUCAGUGUCAGGAAAUUUAUUAAUUUAUUACAUCAAGAACUUAAAUGUUAUUUAAAUGUCUAGAGAGUGCUAGUGUUGUUAAAUUUUCUCAUUUUGAUAAUUAUACUAUGAUUACAGAAGAGAACGUCCUUGUUUUCAGAAAAUGUAAGUAUUUAGAGGUUAAAGGUAAACCUCUAAUUUGGUUUGCCAGUAUUUCAGAUAACUACACACACACACACACACACACACACACACACGGAAUGAUAAAGCAAAAAGUAAGGUGUUGGCAAGGCAUGGUGGCUCACACCUGUAAUUCCAACACUUUGGGAGGCCCAGGCAGGUGGAUCACCUAGGUCUGGAGUUCGAGACCAGCCUGGACAACAUGGUGAAACCCCUCUUUAUUAAAGUACAAAAAUUAGCCGGACAUAGUGGCACAUGCCGGUAAUUCCAGCUAUUUGGGAGGCUGAGGCACAGGAAUCCCUUGAACCUGGAGGCAGAGGUUGUAGUGAGCCUACAUCACACCACUGCACUCCAGCCUGGAUGACAGAGUGAGACUGUCUCAAAAACAAACAAAAAAAAGAUGUUAACAUUUGGGAAAUCUGAGGGAAUGAUGUACAUGAAUUCUUUGUAUUGUUUUUGCAACUUUUAAGUAUAAAGUUAUUUCAGGCCAGGCAUGGUAGUGCAUGCCUGUAUACCCAGCUACUCGAGGCUGAGGUGGAAGAUUCCUUGAGUCUAGGAGUAUGAGGUUACAGUGAGCUAUGAUCAUGCCACUGCACUCCAGGCUGGGUGGCAGAGUGACACCCUAUCUCUUAAAAAAAAAAAAAAAAAAAAAAACAGGUGCAGUAUCUCACACCUGUAAUCUCAACAGAACACUGAGGGGUCAAGGCAGGUGGACUGCUUGAGCCCAGGAGUUCAAGACCAGCCUGAGCAACAUGGUGAAACCCCAUCUCUGCAAAAAAUUAGCUGGUUGUGGUGGCAUCCACCUGUGGUCUCAGCUACUUGGGAGGCUGAGGUGGGAAUAUAACUGGAGCUCAGGAGGUGGAGGUUGCUGUGAGAUGAGAUCGUGCCACUGCACUCCAGCCUAUCUCCAAAAAAAAAAAAAAGGCUAUAGUAGAAGCCUAUUAGCAUGGAUAAGUGUCUGAAUAAAAGAUAACUGUACAAAAAUCAAUUGUUUUUUCUGUAUUCUAGCAAUAAUCAACUAGAAACAGUAUCAAAAGAAAAACAUUCCAUUUACAAUUGCAACAAAUAGGUAUAUAUAUAUUUGCUCUUCUACACAUAACCUAUUUCUGGAAGGGAGCAGAACUGGGCAAUUCAGGGACAGCAAUGGAAGGGGAACACUGCUAUGUUAUUUUAAAUACUUUUUAGUAAGCUUUGAACCAUAUUAAUGUAUUACCUGUUCAAAAUUAUACUUAAUAAAUUUAACAAGAAAACCAUAUUGAAGGGCAUAAAAAUAAGACCUGACAAGUGAAAAAACAUCAAGUUUUAGAAAGGAUGAUUUAAUACUAAAAUAUACAUUUCUUAAUAUAUAACUUAAUGUAAACCUAAUAAAUAAUUUAAUACAAA